AGAGCGGCCCCGGAGCGGCCGCAGCGCGGUGGUCUCGGCCCGGCUGCGCCAGAGUCCGCGCGAUGGAGCCCCGGCCGCGGCGGCGGCGCAGGAGUCGCCCCCUGGUCGCCGCCUUCCUGCGAGACCCGGGCUCGGGCCGCGUGUACAGGCGCGGGAAGCUGAUCGGCAAGGGCGCCUUCAGCCGCUGCUACAAGCUGACAGACAUGUCCACCAGCGCCGUGUUCGCCCUCAAGGUGGUGCCGUGUGGCGGGGCUGGGGCCGGGUGGCUUCGCCCGCAGGGAAAGGUGGAGCGUGAGAUUGCCCUGCAUAGCCGCCUGCGACCCCGCAACAUCGUGGCUUUCCACGGACACUUUGCUGACCGCGACCACGUGUACAUGGUGCUGGAGUACUGCAGCCGCCAGUCUUUGGCCCACGUGCUGAGGGCGCGGCAGAUCCUGACGGAGCCAGAAGUGCGCGACUACCUGCGGGGCCUGGUCAGCGGCCUGCGCUACCUGCACCAGCGGUGCAUCCUGCACCGCGACCUGAAGCUCAGUAACUUCUUCCUUAACAAGAACAUGGAGGUGAAGAUUGGAGACCUGGGACUGGCGGCCAAGGUGGGGCCAGGGGGCCGCUGCCACAGAGUACUCUGUGGGACCCCUAACUUCCUGGACCCUGAGGUUGUCUCCAGAAACGGUCACUCCUGCCAGUAGGACAUCUGGGCUCUGGGCUGCAUCAUGUACACGGUGCUGACUGGCACCCCACCCUUCAUGGCCUCACCCCUGUCGGAGAUGUACCAAAACAUCCGUGAGGGCCACUACCCCGAACCCGCUCACCUGUCUGCCAAUGCGCGCCGCCUCAUCGUGCACCUCCUAGCACCCAACCCGGCCGAGCGGCCCAGCCUGGACCACCUGCUGCAGGACGACUUCUUCACACAGGGUUUCACUCCAGACCGGCUGCCGGCCCACUCCUGCCACAGUCCCCCCAUCUUCGCCAUACCCCCGCCUCUGGGCAGGAUCUUCCGGAAGGUGGGCCAGCGGCUGCUCACCCAGUGCCGGCCACCCUGCCCCUUCACGCCUAAAGAGGCCUCGGGUCCAGGAGAAGGUGGGCCAGACCCUGACUCCAUGGAGUGGGACGGCGAGAGCUCCCUGUCUGCGAAAGAGGUUCCCUGCCUGGAAGGCCCCAUCCACCUGGUCGCACAAGGGACCCUGCAGAGUGACCUGGCCGGGCCCGAGGGGAGCCGGCGGCCAGAGGUGGAGGCGGCCCUCAGACACCUGCAGCUGUGCCUGGAUGUAGGCCCCCCGGCCACACAGGACCCCCUGGGAGAGCAGCAGCCCAUCCUCUGGGCCCCCAAAUGGGUGGAUUAUUCCAGCAAAUACGGCUUUGGCUACCAGCUCUUGGACGGGGGGCGCACGGGACGGCACCCACAUGGCCCUGCGACCCCCCGGAGGGAGGGGACCCUCCCCACACCUGUGCCACCUGCUGGACCCGGCCUCUGCCUCCUGCGCUUCCUGGCCUCUGAGCACGCCCUGCUGCUGCUGUUCAGCAAUGGGAUGGUGCAGGUGAGCUUCAGUGGAGUCCCGGCCCAACUGGUGCUGAGUGGCGAGGGUGAGGGUUUGCAGCUCACCCUCUGGGAGCAGGGGUCCCCUGGCACCUCCUACUCCCUGGACGUCCCGCGGAGCCACGGCUGCGCCCCCACCACCGGACAGCACCUUCACCACGCCCUCCGCAUGCUGCAGAGUAUCUAGUGCCCCUGAGGGUCAGAGUGGACCCCUGCAUGGUAGUGCCAGGGACCCAGGCUCCAUUUCCAUUCCUGUGGCUCCCCCAGAGGGGCUGUCCUGGGGGAGGGCUGGGGGGCACACGGGAGGUGGGUUCUUGCCUUGUGGCAUGACUGUUCAACCCAGACUUUGCUGGGAUCUCUUCCUUUUUCAUUAAAGACAAUUUGAAAUGCUGUAGGCCAUGGUCUGCCUCUCUUUGGGGGAAAGCGUUUGAGGAGCUUUGGCAAAGAAACGUUGACCCCACGUGACGUUGCAUCCUCCCUGUUUCUCUUAGUGGCAGAGGUGGGUUACAUUUUCACUAAUGCAGACAUUAGCACCAGAGGCCAGUGUAGUGGCUCAUGCCUGGAAUCCCAGCACUUUGGGAGGCCAAGGCAGGAGGAUCGCUUGGGCCCAGGAGUUUGAGACCAGCCUGGGCAACAUGGCAAGACCCCAUCUCUACAAAAAAUUAGCUGGGCAUGGUGGCACGUGCCUGUAGUCCCAGCUACUUGGGAGGCUGAGAUGGGAGGAUGGCGUGAGCAUGGGAGGUUGAGGCUGCAGUGAGCUGUGAUUGCACCACUGCACUCCAGCCUGGGCGACAGAACAAAGACCCUGUCUCAACAACAACAAAAGUAGUACCAGAAGUGGGGUUCUGCCAUAACUCCAAAUCUAAAACAUGGGACAGUUGCUUAAUGGGUGGACAGGAAAGAAGCCGACACUGAGGCUGGAAAGAUGGCUGGCUAUGCUCCGGGACACAGUUGGCACAACCGUCACCUGUGCUGCCCUGGGG